GGGCGCCUGCGCGGGCCGGCGCGGGAGCAAGCGGCAUGGCGUUCCGGCAGGCGCUGCAGCUGGCGGCCUGCGGGCUGGCCGGGGGCUCGGCCGCCGUGCUCUUCUCGGCCGUGGCGGUAGGGAAGCCGCGCGCAGGCGGGGACGCGGAGCCACGCCCGGCUGAGCCGCCGGCCUGGGCGGGGGGCGCGCGGCCGGGCCCCGGUGUCUGGGACCCCAACUGGGACAGGCGAGAACCACUGUCUCUGAUCAACGUGCGGAAGAGGAACGUGGAAUCUGGGGAAGAAGAGCUGGCGUCCAAGCUGGACCACUACAAAGCCAAGGCCACGCGGCACAUCUUCCUCAUCAGGCAUUCCCAGUACCACGUGGAUGGCUCCCUGGAGAAGGACCGCACUCUGACCCCGCUGGGUCGGGAGCAGGCUGAACUCACUGGGCUCCGCCUGGCAAGCUUGGGGUUGAAGUUUAAUAAAAUCGUCCAUUCGUCUAUGACGCGCGCCAUAGAGACCACCGAUAUCAUCAGCCGGCACCUGCCAGGCGUCUGCAAAGUCAGCACAGAUCUGCUGCGGGAAGGCGCCCCCAUCGAGCCAGACCCGCCCGUGUCUCAUUGGAAGCCGGAAGCUGUGCAGUAUUACGAAGACGGAGCCCGGAUCGAGGCCGCCUUCCGGAACUACAUCCACCGCGCAGAUGCCAGGCAGGAGGAGGACAGUUACGAGAUCUUCAUCUGUCACGCCAACGUCAUCCGCUACAUCGUGUGCAGAGCACUGCAGUUUCCUCCUGAAGGCUGGCUCCGGCUCUCCCUCAAUAAUGGCAGCAUCACCCACCUGGUGAUCCGACCCAACGGCCGAGUUGCGCUCAGGACCCUCGGGGACACGGGGUUCAUGCCUCCCGACAAGAUCACUCGAUCCUGAGGGCUCCGGCCUCUCCUUCCCUCUGUCCUCCCUGCACAGGCCGCACACACUUAACGUUUUGUUCCCAAGGAGACCGGCGGAAAGUAGAAACCUGCAAUGCUGCAUCUGGGAACUGACUUGUGACCAGGCUGAGAAGGGGAGAGUUGGGAUCAGACAGCCUGACUUCUCUGCAGGGUUUUAUACCUGACCAUGAACCCCCAGGAUGGCGUGGGGUUUAAGGUGAAAGCGUCUCACGCACAAGUCAGGCCUGUUGUGGGGACUUGAAAGAGGCCUGACCCAGACCACCAUGUUCGCACCCACAGCUGACCCGUGCUGAGGGUCCAGGCUCCAUUGGCAAAGCCGGUCAGGCACGAGGGCGACUGAGGCACGUGGAUGAGGAGGGCACCCAGGUUCUGUUCACAACUCACUUCACUUCAUACAUCCUUUUAAUUUCUUAAAACCCUCUUGUCCCUUAAAUAUUUGUCAAUUAAAGAUUUUCUGGCUGGGCACAGUGGCUCACACCUGUAUUCCCAGCUACUCAGGAGGCCAGGGUGGGAGGAUCACUUGAGCUCAGGAGUUCAAGACCAGCCUGGACAAGGCAACAUAGCGAGACCCUGUCUCUACUAAAAAUACAGAACUUAGCUGGGUGUGUCGUGGGCAUCUAGAGUCCCAGCUACUUGGGAGGCUGAGGUGGGUGGAUCACUUGGGCCCGGGAGCUGGAGGCUGCAGUGAGCUGUGAUUGUGUCACUGCACUCCAGCCUGGGCAAGCGAGGGAGACUUAAAGCAAUUUUUUCUUUUGAAACGGAGUUUCACUCUUGUUGCCCAGGCUGGAGUGCAGUGGUGCGAUCUCGGCUCACCGCAACCUCUGCCUCCUGGGUUCAAGUGAUUCUCCUGCCUCAGCUCCCGAGUAGCUGGGAUUACAGUCGCCCACCACCAUACCUGGCUAAUUUUUUGUAUUUUUAGUAAAGACAGGGUUUCAUGGAGAAACCAAUAUAGAAUUGUUCAGGCUGGUCUCGAACUCCCAACCUCAGGUGAUUCACCCACCUUGGCCUCCCAAAGUGCUGGGAUUAAAGGUGUGAGCCAUCGUGCCUGGCCUAAAAAAUUUUUUUUUCUUCAUCUGGGUUUUUGCUUUGAAAACAAGUUUCUCCAAAUUUACAGAUUUCCUGAUGAUGUUGGGUCUGAACUCACCAACUUGAUUAGGUCUUUAGGGGCCGAGGGACUAGCCAGCUGCACAGGUGACUGGAUGGGGGAGGGGCAGGUGAGGUGGGUCUACAGAGGUGGCUUCGCCUUUGACCUUCAUGCUGGUCUCGGCUGAGGUGACACGCUAGUGACAGCCCAAUAGGGGGUUACCCUUAUUGAGUAAAAUACUUCAGAUUGACAGCUCAAUCUUAGUUUGCCUCCAGUUAAUCUUUUAUGCUUAGGGAUUAAAUGUGUGGUUUUUUUUUUGUUUUUUUUUUUUUGGAGACGGAGUCUCGCUCUGUCACCCAGGCUGGAGUGCAGUGGCGCGAUCUCGGCUCACUGCAACCUCUGCCUCCUGGGUUCAAACGAUUCUCCUGCCUCAGCCUCCCAAGUAGCUGGGAUUAUAGGCGCCCACCACCAUGCCUGGCUAAUUUUUUAUUUUUAGUAGAGAUGGGGUUUCACCGUGUUGGCCAGGCUGGUCUCGAACUCCUGACCUCGUGAUCUACCCACCUCGGCCUCCCCAAGUGCUGGGAUUACAGGCGUGAGCUAGCAUGCCUGGCCAGGGAUUAAAAUAUUCAAACAUGUUGUGUGUACCCAGAUAUGCUGUUAAUUUAGGAAAAACAGUACAAUUUCUAUGAAGUGGUUGUGACUAUUUUCUGUAGUCAAUACAGUUGGGAUAUCUGAUCUAUUUCUCUGUCUACUUUGGAAAUGAUUGCAUAAUAAAUAAAAUUUUACUGUUUUUUUAAAA